GUAGCCCCGCGGACAGCUGGGCCAGGGUGCGGGCCUGCGCCUCCCUCGGCUCCUGGCGCGGGCCUCGGGGAGAGGGGUGGAAGAUGUCUAUGGAUGUGACAUUCCUGGGGACGGGUGCAGCAUACCCAUCUCCAACCCGGGGUGCCUCUGCUGUGGUCCUUCGGUGUGAAGGCGAGUGCUGGCUCUUUGACUGUGGGGAGGGAACACAGACACAGCUUAUGAAAAGCCAACUUAAAGCAGGGAGAAUUACCAAGAUCUUCAUCACACACCUUCAUGGAGACCAUUUCUUUGGCCUUCCUGGGCUCCUCUGCACAAUCAGCCUGCAGAGUGGCUCCAUGGUGUCCAAACAGCCUAUUGAAAUCUAUGGCCCUGUAGGGCUUCGGGACUUUAUCUGGCGAACCAUGGAACUCUCUCACACGGAGCUGGUCUUCCAUUAUGUGGUUCAUGAACUGGUUCCUACAGCAGAUCAAUGUCCUGCAGAAGAACUAAAAGAAUUUGCGCAUGUGAAUAGAGCAGACAGUCCUCCCAAAGAGGAACAAGGAAGAACUAUCCUGUUAGACUCAGAAGAAAACUCAUACCUUCUGUUUGAUGAUGAACAAUUUGUUGUAAAAGCAUUUCGCCUCUUUCACAGAAUUCCCUCAUUUGGGUUUUCAGUCGUGGAAAAGAAACGCCCAGGUAAACUCAAUGCACAGAAACUUAAAGACCUUGGUGUUCCACCAGGUCCUGCCUAUGGGAAGCUGAAAAAUGGAAUUUCUGUUGUUCUGGAAAAUGGGGUUACAAUUUCUCCCCAAGAUGUCUUAAAAAAGCCUAUUGUUGGAAGAAAAAUCUGCAUAUUGGGUGACUGCUCUGGGGUUGUGGGUGAUGGAGGAGUAAAACUGUGCUUUGAAGCAGACCUGUUGAUCCACGAAGCAACCCUGGAUGAUGCCCAGAUGGACAAAGCAAAGGAGCAUGGCCACAGCACACCACAGAUGGCAGCAACAUUUGCAAAGUUGUGCCGUGCAAAGAGGCUGGUUCUGACUCACUUCAGUCAGAGGUACAAACCAGUUGCCUUGGCCAGAGAAGGAGAAACAGAUGGCAUUGCAGAACUAAAAAAGCAAGCUGAAUCAGUGUUAGAUCUCCAAGAAGUGACUCUAGCAGAAGAUUUUAUGGUGAUAAGCAUUCCAAUCAAGAAAUGAAACCAGUGUUCCUGAGUGCACACUGACAUGUCUGUGAAUAUGUUACUGAACCUAUAGUCCAGUUUUUUUAUUUCUUGUUUUAGUCUGAAAUUAUUUGGGCCCUAAUAAUCCUAAAAAGAAUGGAGCUGCAUUGAUGAAUUGGCUCAGUAUUUAAAGGGAGCAAACUUUUUGAUAAUAAAUCUUUUUAAGAGAAAAAAAACCCAGCAUCCUUUUUGAAGUCCAGAUUUGUCAAAAUGAUAGACUAUUCAGUUAUACAUCUUAUUUUGUGCUACUACCACAGAUAGCCAAUAUUCCAUGCAGUCCUGGGCUUAGCUUCUGCCCAGCUUUAUUGCUGCUAUUGGCAAAGAGCACAGGACUCAGCCCUCGUGGCUAAAAAUGGUAUUUUGGCAGUUUGUAUUGAAUCUGUUUGUGUUAUUAACAGAAGAGGGAGAAAUGUCAUGAGACGUUGGACAGGCAGGAUUGAUGAUAGCAUGACCAUAGCUUUGCUGGAAUACUGAAUGCAGGGUUUGGCUAGGUGUUUAUUUUAACAUUUUAUUAAACUUUCUAUUUGGGUCUUAACCCAUGGUUCUCAGCUGGGGUGACACUGCUCCUCUAGAAGCAGGUUUGAAAUUAUGGGUAUGUUUUCUUGUCACAGUGACUGAGUACGGUGGUGGUAGUGGUGGUACUACUACUACUGGUAUUUAGUCAGCAGGGAUAAGGGAUGUUAGCUGUCCUGCAAAGUUUUGGUCAGUCAUAUACAAUAAAGAAUCAUCUCACCCCGAAAUGCAAAUUGCAGGCCCAUUGAGAUACACAGCAAGUUAGUUUAUACUCUUGAUGUGAAUAUAGUUUACCAAAAUUAGUGACAUAAUGAGUGGAAUUACUAGGUAAGUCAAAUCCUAAAGAGUGAAUGUGUUAGAAUUGCAGUGUCAUACCAAAUAACAUUCAAAAGAAAUGAGCCAUUAAGUGAAGCUUAUGAACCUGGAGGUAAAAAAUGCUUAUCUGUUAAACUGAGGUUUCAUUGACGUGUCCCUAUUAAUAAACGUUAUUUGCCCCACAA